GUCUUGUAGAAAUGAUUCAGGUUUGGGAUCGCUCUGGUGCCUUGAUGUAGGGAGUCUGGCCUUUCCAGCCUACCAUGCCAGAAGAGGGCUAGAAUAGAUGCUGAAGGAGACGGUCUCUGUGUCUGCUGGGGGUUGGGGUACCCAGAAAGAUCAGGAAUAGGAAGAAACAGUGAUUCUUAACUCCAUUGCUUGGAACCCUGCAGAUUCACUGUCUGGAGAGAAUGAGAAAAAAGAGGCUGGUGCACCCGAGACCAGCUAAAGCAGUGUUGGGGGUCCUCCCAAAGCUGCCCCUGUGGGUUUUGUGCAGUCCAGGUAGAAACCAUUGGAGAUAGUGAGGGGAGCCACGCUGCGGCUUGGGUCAGAGUGGUGACAGAGCAAGUGGGAUGUGGCUGAUGGGAUGAGGCGAUGGGAGCACGGAAGCAGCAGAGGCUGUCUAGGAGAUUGGGAGUCUUUGAUCCCCAUACCAGAGACCAGGUAUGUAGUGCAUCUUGUUGCUGGUGGCUAGUGAUGCCAUCUUAAAUACUAUCGUGUGUGUUUGCUGUUUCAUUAUAGGAUGUGUUAACUUCUUGUUAGAAACUGGGGGGCCGGGCGCGGUGGCUCGUGCCUGUAAUCCCAGCACUUUGGGAGGCCGGGGUGGGCGGAUCACGAGGUAUGUAGAUCGAGACCAUCCUGGCUAACAUGGUGAAACCCUGUCUCUACUAAAAAUACAAAAAAUUAGCCGGGCACGGGCCCCUGUAGUCCUAGCCACUCAGGAGGCUGAGGUAGGAGAAUGGCGUGAACCCAGGAGGCGGAGCUUGCAGUAAGCCGAGAUCACGCCACUGCAUUCCAGCCUGGGCGACAGAGCAAGACUCCGUCUCAAAAAAAAAAAAAGAAAGAAAGUGGGGAUGGGAAGGACUAAGCAAAGAAGACAGUAGUUUUUCAGGGACCGUUAAACACAAUCUUCAGCAAACAAAUCCAGAGCAGCCCUCUUCCCAUGAGAAUAUAUUGGUAGAGUUUUAGGGAGAGAUGAGGAAUUUGGAAUUUCUGGAAAUUAUUGCAGAGGCCUACAGGAUAUGAUCUAGGUCAGUGGUAGUUGAAACUUUUUUUUUUUUUUUAAAAGAAGGAAACCAUUGGAAAAAAAAAUCUUGCUGGUUCCCUGGUCUCUGAGGGCAGUUCCAGACCUUUCUUGGUCUUCCUGUGCUCACAAUUGGGCUUCUGAGGAGUCUCUCAGCAUCCCCAGAACUGCUGUCCUGGUCUUUCCAGUGGCCAUUGUGGGUCUCUUUGAAGUUGAAUCUGCCCUUGACGUCCACCACACUCUGUUCUCUGACUAAUUAGAGAGGGCAAACGGGAGGGUGAGAGUCCAGGAGGGAAACCCGGAAUGGCUUCUGCUGAGGUAGAGGGGGAUCAGUUUGAAGUGAGGAAAGCAACUUUGAAGCAAGGAUAAAGAUGAGAACUGGGCACUUGGAGGGAUUCUGGGGCUAGGGCUUGGUGACACUGAUGCCUCCUGUUCCCACAGAAACCUGCAAGAUGGCUUAGGGAUGCAGGGCAAUAGAGCAAGGGAUCCAGGCUGAGGGGGCCGAAGGGAGGCACGUGAGGAGCUGUAUUCAGAACUUUCUGUCCCACCUACAAAGAUUUUCCUUUUGGCAUUCCACUCAGAUCCCCCCUGUUUUUACCUCAACCUUAGGGCUUCCUUGCUUUGGUUACUGUUAGCACCAUGAUUUGUUCCUAAGGGAUCGUAACACCUUAAAAAUCCCAGUCCAAGUGCUGUAAGAGACACCUUUCUCCAGGCCUCCUCAACACAGUUUCUUUUGAAGACUGCUCUUCUCUUUCAACUUUAUUUACAGGUGAAGGAAGUGUGCAGUAGAGAAGUUACAGCUUCUCACAGCUAGUGGGAACAGUAAUCAAGGCUAGGAAACCUGAGUCAUCUUGUUGGCUGUGUGCCCCAAAUAGAAAGAACGCUUUCUGGCCAGGUGCAGUGGCUCACACCUGUAAUCCCAGCACUUUGGGAGGCCGAGGAGGGCGGAUUAUGAGGUCAGGAGAUGGAGACCAUCCUGGCCAACAUGGUGAAACCCCGUCUCUACUAAAAAUACAAACAUUAGCUGGACAUGGUGGCGUGUGCCCGAAAUCCCAGCUACUUGGGAGGAUGAGGCAGGAGAAUCGCUUGAACCAGGGAGGUAGAGGUUGCAGUGAGCCGAGAUCACGCCAUUGCACUCCAGCCUGGCAACAGAGCGAGACUCUGUCUCAAAAAAAAAGAGAGAAUACUUUCUAAUACCUCAGCUGUCACAAGUGAUGCCUCCUGUACUGUGAGCCAGAGGGGUCAGCCCAAAGGGAAGGGAGGCCUUAUCGAAAAGGGCAGAUGCCUGAGGCCCCCUCUGUUGGUUGCACCUUGGGGCCAGGAUUCUGACUGUAGCACUCAAUGUCUUAUUUGAUGUUUCUGUUUCGUUCAUAUUAUGAAUUACUAGGUCAUGGUUUAGUCUUAAUAAGAUUCCUCAUUUGUAUUAAUAAAGGUCAGCUUAUUUGCACGUGGACUGUAGUUGGAUUUUUCCCAUUUCUGUGUGUAUGCAUUCCCAGUUAGAGCUCCUUCUGUAAGAAGACUGAAGCUUAAGUAAGACACAGCCUGGGUUUAUGACUGGUGUCUUAAUUUGUUUUCUGCUGCUUUAGCAGAAUAUCAAGCUGGAUAAUGAACAGAAAUUUAUUAGGCUCUUGGUUCUGGAGGUUAGGGAAGUCCAAGAGCAUGGCGAUGGCAUCUCGUGAGGGCUUUUGGGCUCUAUCCUCUUGUGAUGGAUGGUGGAAGGGCAGCGAGUGCGUCAGAGAGAAAGGGGGCUGAACUUGUCCUUUUUAUCAGGAACCCACUUUCAUAAUAAAGCCGUCACCUAUUAAAUGUCCCACCUCUCAGUGCUGUUAAAAUGACAAAUUUUAACGUGAGCUUUGGAGAGGACAUAUGAAAACAUAUUAGCUGGUCAUGCUGGAGAAGUUGGGGAUCAGAACAUCAAAAUAUGGCAAGGCGUGGUAACUCAUGCCGGUAAUACCCGCACUUUGGGAGGCCGAGGCAGGUGGAUCACCUGAGGUCAGGAGUUCGAGACCAGCCUGGCCAGCAUGGCAAAACCCCAUCUCUACUAAAAAUACAAAAAUUAGCUGGGCGUGGUGGUGCACGCCUGUAGUCCCAGCUACUAGGGAGACUGAGGCAGGAGAAAUGCUUGAACCCAGGAGGCGGAGGUUGCAGUGAGCCGAGAUCUCACCACUGCACUCCAGCGUAGGCAACAGAGCAAGACUCUGUCUUAGAAAAAAAAAAGAACAUCAGAAUGUGAAAAAACCUGAAAUGAAUUUAGAAGUUUAAAACAGUUUCUUACAACAAAAAAUAAUAGCUUUUAAGUCAAAAUAUGUAAUGUAGGAAAUGUCGGAAUUCAGUGAAAAUGAGUGACCUUUACAUAGGCUUAGCUGUUCACUGGUAGCAGCAAAAAUAGGCCCUUGAGUCCAAGCUAGACUUGAAUUCUGAUUCUUCCAGACUUUGUGCAGUGAAGUCAGAUGAGGGUAACAGGACCUAGCGUGUGAUACCCUUAGCACUCUUACUACUCUUGCUAAGUAAUUAUGUGAUUAGAGUUUGGAAUGAAACUUCCAGAAAUGUUAUAAUUGAGGCUUGGCGCGGUGGCUUAUGCCUGUAAUCCCAGCACUUCGGGAGGCUGAGGUGGGUGGAUCAUGAGGUCAGGAGUUCGAGACCAGCCUGGUCACCAUGGUGAAACCUUGUCUCUACUAAAAAUACAAAAAUUAGCUGGGCGUGGUGGUAGAUGCCUGUAAUCCCAGCUACUCGGAAGGCUGAGGCAGGAGAAUCGCUUGAAACGGAGGUUGCAGUGAGCCGAGGUCGCGCCACUGCACUCUAGCCUGGGCAACAAGAGUGAAACUCUGUCCCCCUCCAAAAAAUAAAUAAAAAUAAAAUAUAUAAUUGUUACCUAUCAAAAUUCUGAGGGAAAGCCAGGCGUGGUGGCUCACACCUAUAAUCCCAGCACUUUGGGAGGCCGAGGCGGGUGGAUCAACUGAAAUCAGGAGUUCAAGACCAGCCUGGCUAACGUGAUGAAACCCCGUCUCUACUAAAAAUAGAAAAAUUAGCCAGGUGUGGUGACACACACCUGUAAUCCCAGCUCUUCGGAAGGCUGAGGCAGGAGAAUCGCUUGAACCUGGGAGGCAGAGGUUGCAGUGAGCCAAGAUCAUGCCAUUGCACUCCAGCCUGGGCGAUGAAAGUGAAACUCUGUCUCAAAAGACGACAACGAUAAAAAAAACAAAGUUCUGCGGGAAGAAGACAACUAGAGACAUGCUGUUGGCCACACAUAGUGCUCUUGGGGCUGCUUAAGUCUGUGGAGUUCUGGGGAAGAAGCUGGUUUUCCCAUGGGCUAUGCAGCAGCAGCUCCUGCCUAUUCUCCUAACAUGUAUCCUGGAGCGAAUCCUACCUUCCAAACAGGUUACACUCCUGGCACACCUUACAAAGUGUCCUGUUCCCCCACCAGCGGGGCUGUGCCACCGUACUCCUCCUCCCCGAACCCCUACCAGACUGCCGUGUACCCUGUGCGAAGUGCCUACCCCCAGCAGAGCCCGUAUGCACAGCAAGGCACGUACUACACACAGCCGCUGUAUGCAGCACCUCCUCACGUCAUCCACCACACCACGGUGGUGCAGCCCAACGGCAUGCCUGCAACGGUGUACCCUGCUCCCAUCCCCCCUCCUAGAGGCAACGGGGUCACCAUGGGCAUGGUGGCUGGGACCACCAUGGCCAUGUCAGCAGGUACCCUGCUGACUGCUCACUCCCCAACUCCUGUCGCCCCCCACCCGGUCACUGUGCCCACGUACCGGGCCCCAGGAACGCCCACUUACAGCUAUGUGCCCCCUCAGUGGUGAUCACCUGCAAAUGUUUGAGGACGGAGCUGUGCAGUCACAUUAUUGGGGAUUCCACAGCUGGUGCUGCAGGCCUUGCGCCUCCAACCAGGACUUUCUUCUUAAUGCUCUCGACACUUAGCUAAACACGACUAUAUCCCGGCCCAGCAGGCCCCAGCGCCGUUAGUCUCCAGCUGACUCUGUGGGUUGGUCUUAAAGCAAAUUCUGUUUUGUGGACUGCCUGGCAAUUUUUUAGCUAACUGUAAUGAUAAAAAGGGAGUAUUAAUCUAUUCUGAAUCAUAUCUAGUUGAAUGCAUGUUUAAAAAAACAAACACAAAAAGCUUGCUCAAUCUACCUGCAGUGACUGAUGCAAAACCAUCAUAUGCAAAAUCCAAAGGAAUGGAAACGUAUUUUACAACUUGUAUCACUAAUGCACUGUUGUAAUGUAUGCAAAGUCUUACAGUUAUAAGUGUUAAAGUGAAUUUCUUCAUAGAGCAUCUGAAAUAUCUUAGAUGAUUCUUCAACCUUUUGGGGUUGAUGUGGGUUGCCAGUUAGGGAUGUGGACAUUUUAGUUUUCAGCGACCUGUUUCUUUGGCACUGACUGUCCUGGGAGGGAGUUGCGAGGUUUGGGAGAGAGUAGGGAAGCCACAGCUGCUUGGGUGCAGCUGGUUCAUGGACAUCCCUUUGAGUUUAGGCUUGGUGGAGUCAGUGGAACAGGGACAUGCUUAAAGCUCAUCAUGAAAGAUUAUGGUAGUGUGGCCAGUGAAAUUUGGGGCGAGGGGGGUGGUUUAUGUGUCAGCAAAGCAGUUUCUCUGCUAUCUAAAUUUUCAUUACAGUUCUCUUAGAGAGAUGAUGUUUUUAUAUGUCUUUAUUGGAAAAGUCCUAUGUAAAACUAAAUUAUUUUCCUGGGAUGGAAGAAAUGUGAAAGAGAAACAGCCAUGCUUGCAGGAGGUAUUGUCCUCUGCUUUAUUUAGCUUAGAAAAUCAUUCCUUUUUUUUUUUUUUUCCUGGAGAAAUGUUUGAAUCAGCUGAAAACAGGUAGGCAUUGCUGUUUUUCCCCAACAAAGAAGGGCAAAGGUUUCAGCUGUAUGUUAUGAAGAAAGUGGUAUAUUUAAGAAUGAGUUAAAAGGGAACAAAACUUUAUUUAAAAUUCCUCCAAUUUCUUGUAGAAAGGCAGGGCCGUGGAUAUGUCUGGAAAUGUAGAAACCUGUAGCUGCUUCUGGGAUCACCCACCUGAUGGUGGUGACUUGUCUGCUGAGGCCGGCUGGAGGGGACGCUUAGAGAUGGGGCGAGGGGGAGGCCAGUGUCUGUUGUCUGCGAGCCUCUCCUGCCAUCUCUUUUGCAGCUGAGGGCACUUGGCACAAAGCAAGCACAGACAGCAGAGAGGGCCAGGCAGUGCUGGAGUGCGUUUGCUGGCAGGGUUUAUUGUGGGAGAGGAAUUUGAGUUUAGGAUCUGAAUCUUGUACAUAAGAAAUGAAAAGGCUUCCCUCCACCCCGCCCCCAAAAUAUGCCCGUCCUGUAUCCAUGAGAGUGCAUGUCGGUUCUCAGUGAGGGUCAGAGUGGGGGUGGGGGAUGUAAGGCCUGGGUCCCUUUCAGCGGCCUCUAGGGCAGGAGCGUGCGUCUUCUUCCCAGUGCAGUGGUGGUUUGAGUGCUGUGGGCUCUGGUGGGGAGGGGGCUCUGCUCCUCUUCAUUUGCUGGUAGCUGGGUCAGGGCACUGGCGCCCAGUGAGGAUGCCCACUAGCAUUCUGCCCCAGUUGGUUGGUGGGGGGACACCUGACCACUGAGCCUUUGGUAACCUUAUUUUUUAUAGUAAGUACUUCUUAUAAUUUUCUUUUUCACAUCUUAUUUUAUAAGAAGUUUAGGAAUAUUUUUGCAUGGAUCAUUGUAAACAGCAGAUUCUUUAUUCCUGAUGUCUAUUAACAUAGAAUGUUUACUGAUAAGUACUUUAAAUUGCUUCAUGAGCACUUAAUCCAUCUUAGUGUCUAUGUGUGGGGGCAGACAUUUACCGCAGGCACACAGUUUGUGCCCCUUUCUUCAAGUCUCUGUUGGUAAUUCCAUCUGUUUAGUGGAUGGUUGGCAGGAUUAGUAGGUUCUAACGGUUCCAGGGGUUCAGCUGACCAAGUAGCAGAGAAGUCUUUUUUCCCAAUUGAGUGCUAAUAGAUUAGGAUAAAAUACUCACAAUGUUAGUGUAUGCUUUUAAAAAGCCCCACACAACAAAAUGGAAACAUACAUGUACAACUCCUGUGAGGGCUGGAGUCUUGGGGUUCAGGAGGAGGUUAGAAGUUACAGGCAUCUCUUCAGGCUUGCUUGGUACUUGGCACACACAGGAUGGUGUUUUAAAGAGUGGGCUGCACCCCCCACACGCCAUUUACAUCAGCUUCAUAAACACUUUUCUUCCUCCCUGUAACUUAACCUUUUUUCCCUUUUAUGAAGUUGAGAGGCUUUAUGAAAUAAGUUUGCAUUGCACAUCCGUGCAGAAAUCUUUCUGACUUUGAAAUUUUUAGGACGUCAGCUGUCAGAUACGAAAGGUAGAUAUCAGGUAAGAAUCUGGACUUAGGAAAUAGUCACAAAACUGUCAUAGGUUGUAAUUUUAUCAACAUUCGCUUCUAGUAAAAUUAAAGUCAAUUAAGAAAUAGAACUUGGGUCAAAAUUCUGUUACAAAGCUUCAUAAUUUGUCCCGAAGCAUAUGGUGGAGCAUUCUGAGAAAUUUGCUUUUUGUGUGUUUGACAUUCCUAAUUUGGGAGUCCUUCAGCUGAAUUACUAUUCUUUUAGAAGUUGAGACAGCAGGUAAGCAAAGGACCUAGUUCAUGUAAACAUGGACAUCAUGAUGGCUAUUUAAAAAAUAUUUGUUCUACACCUUCUCCCCUGAGGCUUGGGGAGUGUGUUCAGCCGCUGCAGUUUCUCUGCUCAUGGAGGUCUUGUUUGGAUCUGUGCUGGCGGCUGAGCAUUUAGUGUGAGCCAGUGACCCAUGAACUUGCCGCUCUGUGAGGGCCAGAGUCAGGGCCAGUCAUGGUAAUGGGCCUGAAGGCACUUCCAGAACCUUUUAUGUCUCUCGUGAGCCAUCUGUUAAGAACGUUCUUCUUGGUGUGGUUUGUAGGCCUACCUGUCGCUAUUCUGGGAAACCUUCUUGAGUGCUAUGCAAAUGUGUUCACAGGCAAUGGGGGUGGUCCUGAGCCUUGGGGUGGGCACCUGGUCAGUGAGUGUCUUGCCCUUCCCCAGCUGGGCAUACAGUACCUUGCUCUUUCUGGUGGCAUCAUCUGGCUGUGAUGAAUGAGGUCUAGGAAAUAAUUUGCAUGUGUCUUGGGGGACACAACAGUAACGAGAGGAAAUACAUUAUUACAGCAACUUGCGACGUACUAAUACCUGUCAGUGUUGGCCCCCGUAAGGUAUGUAAGGCACCUGUGAGUGCCAGUGAGUGCUGGUGAAAGGCCAACAUGUACUAGUUAUGUAAGUAUUGGUGUCUGCUUUAAAAAAGGAGACCCAGACUUCACCUGUCCUUUUUAAACAUUUGAGAACAGUGUUACUCUGAGCAGUUGGGCCACCUUCACCUUAUCCGACAGCUGACUGUUGGAUGUGUCCAUUGUCGCCAGUUUGGCUGUUGCCCGGACAGGACAGGACCUCCAUUGGGCGCAGCAGCAGGUGGCAGGGGUGUGGCUUGAGGUGGGUGGCAGCGUCUGGUCCUCCUCUCUGGUGCUUUCUGAGAGGGUCUCUAAAGCAGAGUGUGGUUGGCCUGGGGGAAGGCAGAGCACGUAUUUCUCCCCUCUAGUACCUCUGCAUUUGUGAGUGUUCCCUCUGGCUUUCUGAAGGGCAGCAGACUCUUGAGUAUACUGCAGAGGACAUGCUUUAUCAGUAGGUCCUGAGGGCUCCAGGGGCUCAACUGACCAAGUAACACAGAAGUUGGGGUAUGUGGCCUAUUUGGGUCGGAAACUGCAUGUUUCAGAAAGUUUGUCUCUUUUUCCUACUCAUUAUUUGAAGAAGAGAGAGCCUGUGGGGAUAGCCUUAUCUUGGUCCACAGGACUGAAGUGAAGUCACUUGGGAAGGGGAGACAGAGGAUGAGCGGCGUCUGUGUAGGGACCCCCCCCCGGGCCUGCAGAAGGGUGGUGUGCUCCCAGGACUGGCAUGACAGGUGUCUCCUCCUCACCACAGGCUGUGCCCAUGAGUCCCUGUGCAGACCAGUGGGCAAGGCAGCUGGGCCAGAUCUCAGGCCAGCCGUUUGUGCUCCUAGCAGGGUUGCUGUGCUGGCCACACGGAGAGGCCCUAGAGAGCCUCAUGGAUUGUAACUAAAGAAGAAACGGUUCCUUUUUGUUUUUUUAAAAAUGAUUUUUAAAUACCGUUUUUUACACCGUUCUCUCGGUACUUUUUUUAAGCUAAGUCAGCAUUGUCUUCCAGUGUUAAAGGCAUCCCUCACCUCUGCAUUGAACUUACGUAUCCAUGCCAAGGAAUGGAAUUUCCAUCCUGAGCCAGUUCAGUUAGGUGUCAAUUGAUACUAUUUUAAUUUUUUAUGCAAUCUGAUGAGAUGAGCUCAGAUUUAAAAAUCUCAAAAGCACGUUUAUUGUAACAAGAAUUGUUAUGUAUUAAUACUGCAGUUUUCAAUAAAGAUUGACUUGUGUUGCA